CCUUUCCUUUCAGCGGAGCGCGGCGGCAAGAUGGCAGUGCAAAUAUCCAAGAAGAGGAAGUUUGUCGCUGAUGGCAUCUUCAAAGCUGAACUGAAUGAGUUUCUUACUCGGGAGCUGGCUGAAGAUGGCUACUCUGGAGUUGAGGUGCGAGUUACACCAACCAGGACAGAAAUCAUUAUCUUAGCCACCAGAACACAGAAUGUUCUUGGUGAGAAGGGCCGGCGGAUUCGGGAACUGACUGCUGUAGUUCAGAAGAGGUUUGGCUUUCCAGAGGGCAGUGUAGAGUUGAAAAUAAUGGUGAUGGUAACAGGAUAUCCCUUGCUUCCUUUAAAGCUUUAUGCUGAAAAGGUGGCCACUAGAGGUCUGUGUGCCAUUGCCCAGGCAGAGUCUCUGCGUUACAAACUCCUAGGAGGGCUUGCUGUGCGGAGGGCCUGCUAUGGUGUGCUGCGGUUCAUCAUGGAGAGUGGGGCCAAAGGCUGCGAGGUUGUGGUGUCUGGGAAACUCCGAGGACAGAGGGCUAAAUCCAUGAAGUUUGUGGAUGGCCUGAUGAUCCACAGCGGAGACCCUGUUAACUACUACGUUGACACUGCUGUGCGCCACGUGUUGCUCAGACAGGGUGUGCUGGGCAUCAAGGUGAAGAUCAUGCUGCCCUGGGACCCAACUGGUAAGAUUGGCCCUAAGAAGCCCCUGCCUGACCACGUGAGCAUUGUGGAACCCAAAGAUGAGAUACUGCCCACCACCCCCAUCUCAGAACAGAAGGGUGGGAAGCCAGAGCCGCCUGCCAUGCCCCAGCCAGUCCCCACAGCAUAACAGUUUCUUACUUUUGUGCUUUAUUUGGUUUCAGGGUCUCCUUGGCAGCUGUAUUCUGGAGUCUGGAUGUUGCUCUCUAAAGACCUUUAAUAAAAUUUUGUACAAAGACACAAGGUCUGACUAGACUGUUCAGUAUUCAGACUGAGGGGCAUGUUGGCCUCUGGAGCAUUACAUAUCUUCUUGGUUUUAACCAUACUUGUGGUAUUUGCAAGGGCCAGAACAGUAAGACCCAAGCAGAGCCAACCAGAGAAAUAAUAUUUGUGUGAUAGAGAAGGCUGAUAGCAAGCAAGGCAGCACCUUGAUUCGUUGUCCUGUAGUUCAGGAUUGUAGGUUUAGAAGAGGGAUAUGUUUGAGUUUUUCCUAUGCAUAAGGCGAUCCACGUUGCACAUAGAAAGUGAAUAUAAAUGGCCAUUAUAUUUUGUGUCAUGCUGUGCUCUAAGUGUUCUUUACAUAUGUACUCGUUAAUCAACCUCUCUAAAGUGUAAAGGAAAUUUGCUUGCACCACUGAAGGCACAUAAGGCUCAGAAGUAAAUUUGCCUAAGCAGUAUAAAGCUAUCAUUAGAAUCCACAUUCCUAAGUUGUGUUCUCUUAGGGGAUCAUGGAACCAGUCAUUGGUACUACAGGCUAUUAUGUUCUGGAGAACUGUGAAGAACAUUUAAAUUGUCUCUGAUUUUAUCUAUCAAUGUUUUGAAGUAUUUUCUACCAGUGUCUGUACUUCACAAGAAAUUCGGCACUAUUUUUUCAGGCAAAACUAGUGAGGGACAGGUUGGCUUGAAAAUCAUGAGACUGUUGUUAAAUCAGAUGCUGGUUGAUCACAGAGGGGACUUCCAGGGAAAGCUGUUAUCAGGUGGCUGCUUCCUGGUGAUGCAGCCUGGCUGAUGAGAUAACCCUGGCUCCACAGAUGGCUUAGCAGGUGCUGUGAUGAUUUGGUUUUCUUCUCAAUUAGACUGAGCUGCACAUGGUGUUUAUAUUGCUUGGCACAUGGUAAGGGCUUAAUAUUUGAGGUAAUUAUGUAGGGCGUACACUGACAAGUAUCUGACCCCCCCUUCCUUUUUGACUCAUAAAUUGGUCAUCUUAACCAUUUAAGUGUACACUUCUAUAGUGACAGAGUUAGCCCUCUGUCCAAGGGAUUUGCAUCUGUGGAUUCAACCAACUUUGGGUCAAAAAUAAUCAAAAAGGAUGGUUGUGUGUGUAUUGAACAUGUAGACUUAUUUUUCUUAUUUUCAAAAUACUAUAUUUUCUUGUCACUUAUUUUCUUGUACACUGCAGUUGUAACAGCUAUGUAGCAUGUACAUUAGGUAUUAAAAGUAAUCCAGUGAAGAUUGAAA